AGCCUCGCCCUCCGCCACGAUGAGCAAAUGAGCGCGAGCGAGGGCAUGAAAUUUAAAUUCCACUCAGGGGAGAAAGUGCUGUGCUUCGAGCCUGACCCCACCAAGGCGCGAGUGCUGUACGAUGCCAAGAUUGUUGAUGUUAUUGUUGGGAAAGACGAAAAAGGCAGAAAGAUCCCAGAAUAUCUGAUCCAUUUUAAUGGUUGGAACAGAAGCUGGGAUAGAUGGGCAGCAGAAGAUCAUGUGCUUCGUGAUACCGAUGAAAAUCGUAGAUUACAGCGUAAAUUGGCAAGAAAAGCUGUAGCUCGCCUGAGGAGCACAGGAAGAAAGAAGAAGCGCUGCAGGUUGCCUGGUGUGGACUCUGUCUUAAAAGGCCUCCCCACUGAAGAAAAAGAUGAAAAUGAUGAAAACUCAUUAAGCAGUUCCUCUGACUGUAGUGAAAACAAGGAUGAAGAAAUAAGUGAAGAAAGUGAUAUUGAAGAAAAGACUGAAGUGAAAGAAGAACCAGAGCUUCAAACAAGAAGGGAAAUGGAAGAAAGAACAAUAACUAUAGAAAUCCCUGAAGUUCUGAAGAAGCAGCUGGAGGAUGAUUGUUACUACAUUAACAGGAGGAAACGGUUAGUGAAACUUCCAUGCCAGACCAACAUCAUAACGAUUUUGGAAUCCUAUGUGAAGCAUUUUGCUAUCAAUGCAGCCUUUUCAGCCAAUGAGAGGCCUCGUCACCAUCACGUUAUGCCACAUGCCAACAUGAACGUGCAUUAUAUCCCAGCAGAAAAGAAUGUUGACCUUUGUAAGGAGAUGGUGGAUGGAUUAAGAAUAACCUUUGAUUACACUCUCCCGUUGGUUUUACUCUAUCCAUAUGAACAAGCUCAGUAUAAAAAGGUGACUUCGUCUAAAUUUUUUCUUCCAAUUAAGGAAAGUGCCACAAGCACUAACAGGAGCCAGGAGGAACUCUCUCCCAGUCCGCCUUUGUUGAAUCCAUCCACGCCACAGUCCACAGAGAGUCAGCCGACCACCGGUGAACCAGCCACCCCCAAAAGGCGCAAAGCUGAGCCAGAAGCAUUGCAGUCUCUGAGGCGGUCCACGCGCCACAGUGCCAACUGUGACAGGCUUUCUGAGAGCAGCGCUUCACCUCAGCCCAAGCGCCGGCAGCAGGACACAUCCGCCAGCAUGCCCAAGCUCUUCCUGCACCUGGAAAAGAGUAGGUUCAUUCUCGGGUGCCCCAGGCCGGGGAGAGCCAGCGUGUACUUUGUGUUUAGUCAGUGCCAGGCAUGGUGCUGAGGUUACAUGUGUGUGUGUACAGUGCGUGUGAUUCCCAUGUCCAAAGUGCUGUCAUGCUGCCUGCUUUCUGGAGCUGUAGAAAGUUGAAACACCUGGCGCAGAUUGCAGCGCAGCUGUGUUGGAGGCAGGACUGGGCUGUUUCCUCAGCCUUUCUUUUUUGCCAUCACUCUACCACUUGUGAGCAAAUUGAGUUAUCAGAAUUCUAUGUAUUGUGUAGCUAGGCCUAAUGAAGCAUUCAAAAUGAGCAAUGCUAAUGGGUUGUUUAGCUUUUUGUUUUCUUUGUACUCUGUCUCUGUAGUCUCUCCAUUCUAAAGUUUAAUUUGGAAAGGUCUGUCCUGAAUUAUCAAAGUAAGAAUACUCAGAUUUCCAUAAGCUCUUCUCACCUCCUCUUAGCCCAACUCAAACUCCAUCAGAUCUUCUCACCUUGAUUUUGAGCUGGAAUGUUUCAAUGAGCAAAAUAAAUUAGACAAAAGUUUACUUUCUUUUUUUCCAAAAUACACACAGGUUGAUUUGCUGUAAUAUAAAACUUAGAAGUAAACCACUGCUAAUUAAUCAUUUUAAACUUUCAAAAACUGCUAAAACAGGUGCCAUGAAUCAGGUACAAUUACUGUAGAAACUAACAUUAGCUAUUAUACACUAACCAGGCAUUUUUCCCAAAUUAAUUACAAUCUGGUUGUUUAGCCUAUGCUAAUUAAGCCCUCUUAGUAGUAGUAUUCACUUUACAUUGAAGACCUCAUUCACAAAUACAGGGUGCUCUGUGCUUAUAUCCUUCCACCCUUGACUGCCAAAAAUGUGUGAAAUGGAAAGUUGAUGGCAGCAGGGCCGACGAUGUCACCUGGUGCCUCGCGGGCUCAGUGAGUUAGGAAGUCAGCAGCAGGGGAGGCAGCUUGCAUGCCUGUCCCCCGGCACACUGUGUGGAGGUGGAAACAGAGCUACGCCAGCAGGCGCCAAGCACCCAACUCCAGAGAUGGAAGCCUGGUGGCCUUCCUUUCACAGAGCUCAGCUGCUCGCAGGCUGUGAAAUCUAAGACACCCCUCAUAAAUAUCAAAAACACCUCCAAAGCUAACGUCAGGGUAAAACUACUUGGAGUCGAAUCCCCAUGCCCCAGUAGGUGUAUCUUGUGUAUGACCUGUGCCCUGUUCUUCCCUCAGCCUCGCCUGCUGUGCUGACUCCUUCAGGGGUCCUUCUAAGCAUCAUCCUGUUGGAACUCCCAAAAGUCAUCCCAGUGCCAUUCUGUGUUCAGGUGCCCAUUUCCUUGUGUACAUCCUGUCCCUGCCACAUCCAUAAGCUCCUGAGAGAAAGGUCUGACUUGUUGAUUGUGUCACCCCAUCACAGCUCAGUGUUGGUGGCAUAGUUCCAGGUGCGUGAAAGUAUUUGCUGAUUCUUUGAAGAUUGGGAAGGCUCAGAAGGGCAGAGUUGAAGAAGGCAUACCUUUAAGAGAAGCCCUUUGAAUAAUCAAGUGCUAAAACAAAAUCAGGUGCUUUUUUAAAACAGCUUGAUUGAGAUAUAAUCCACAUACCUUAAAAUUCACACAUUUAAAGUUUUUAGUGUCUCCAGACACAGUGGUUCAUGCCUGUGAGACUGGGGCAGGAGGAUCACUUGAGGCCAGGAGUUCAAGAUCAGCCUGGGCAAUAUAGUGAAACCCCAUCUCUUAAAGAAAAAGUUAGCCAGGUGUGAUGAUGUGCACCUAUAGUCCCAGCUACUUGGGAGGCUGCAGCUGUGGCUGUGGCUGAAGCUGGCGGAUCGCUUGAGGCCCAGAGUCUAAGACUGCAGUGAGCUCUCAUUGGGCCACUGCAGUCGAGCCUGGGCGACACAAAGAGACCACCCUGUCUGAUAGAUAACUAACAAAAUAGUUUUAGUUGGGCAAAAUUAAAGAGUUGGGCAACCAUCACUGAAAUCAGUUUCAGACAUUUUCACCACUCCAAAAAAGAAACCCCACAUCGACUAGCAGUUACUCAUUUGCUUCUCCCUAUGUCCCCUGACAACCACUAAUCUAUUUGUCUCUAUAGAUUUGCCAGUUUGGGGCAUUUCAUAUAAAUGGAAUCAUCUGUAUGUAAGUGGUUAAUAAGGAUUGGUUGAUUGAAGAUUGAAAAGGGUCAGCUGGGAAAAUUUUUAAAAAGACUGUUUUUAAAAAGGUGCUACAAAAUAAAGUGCUAUCUUUUUCUGUU